AGUACUCGGCCGUCAGAGGGAGCUGCCAGGCUCUGGAGGGCGCCCCGGAAACCAUGGAAGUCCUCGUCCUGGCCGGAUACCGCGCGCAGAAGGAGGACGAGCUGAGUCUGGCGCCCGGGGACGUGGUCCGGCAGGUGCGCUGGGUGCCCGCGCGGGGCUGGCUUCGCGGAGAGUUUGGGGGCCGCUAUGGCCUCUUCCCCGAGCGCCUGGUGCAGGAGAUCCCAGAGACCCUGCGGGGCUCCGGAGAGGCGCGGAGGCCGCGCUGUGCGCGCCGCCGAGGUCAUCCUGCCAAACACCCGAGGCCCCAAAGAUGGUGCAAAGUGAACUUCAGCUACAGCCCAGAGCAGGCGGACGAGCUGAAGCUGCAAGCUGGGGAGAUCGUGGAAAUGAUAAAGGAGAUUGAGGACGGCUGGUGGCUGGGGAAGAAGAACGGGCAGCUGGGAGCCUUCCCAUCCAACUUUGUGGAAUUGCUGGACAGUGGGCCCCCAAGCCUUGGUAACCCAGACAUGCCUUCAGUCAGCCCUGGUCCCCAGCGGCCUCCCAAGCUGAGCAGCCUGGCCUAUGACAGCCCUCCAGACUACCUGCAGACAGUCUCCCACCCUGAGGUCUACAGGGUCCUGUUUGACUACCAGCCUGAGGCCCCAGACGAGUUGGCGCUGCGGAGGGGGGACGUGGUAAAAGUACUCAGCAAGACCACAGAGGAUAAGGGCUGGUGGGAAGGAGAGUGUCAAGGACGAAGAGGAGUUUUUCCAGACAACUUUGUACUCCCACCACCCCCAAUCAAGAAGCUGGUCCCACGGAAAGUGGUAUCUCGGGAAUCAGCUCCUAUUAAGGAACCAAAAAAGUUGAUGCCCAAAACAUCCCUCCCCACAGUCAAGAAGCUAGCAACAGCCACCACUGGGCCCAGCAAAGCCAAGACAUCUCGGACACCCAGCAGGGACAGUCAGAAGCUCACCUCCCGAGACUCAGGCCCCAAUGGUGGCUUCCAAAGUGGGGGUUCGUAUCACCCUGGCCGAAAGCGAUCCAAAACCCAGACUCCCCAGCAACGCUCUGUGUCCAGUCAGGAGGAAGAGCACAGCAGCCCGGUAAAGGCCCCCUCUGUGAAGAGAACCCCCAUGCCGGACAAGACUGCCACCCCAGAGAGGCCCCCAGCUCCAGAGAACGCCCCCAGCUCCAAGAAGAUCCCGGCUCCUGACAAAGUCCCCUCCCCAGAGAAGACCCUCACUCUAGGGGACAAGGCCUCUAUCCCAGGGAACUCCACCUCGGGGAAGAUCCCAGCUCCUGACAAAGUCCCCACCCCAGAGAAGAUGGUGACUCCGGAGGACAAGGCUUCUAUCCCAGAGAACUCCAUCAUCCCAGAGGAGACCCUGACUGUGGACAAACCCUCCACUCCAGAGAGGGUCUUUUCAGUGGAAGAGUCCCCUGCCCUAGAAGCCCCACCUAUGGAUAAAGUCCCUAAUCCAAAGAUGGCCCCUCUGGGGGAUGAGGCCCCCACUCUAGAAAAGGUCUUGACCCCAGAGCUUUCUGAAGAAGAGGUGUCCACCAGAGAUGACAUUCAAUUCCAUCACUUCUCUUCGGAGGAAGCCCUGCAGAAGGUCAAGUACUUUGUAGCCAAAGAGGAUCCAUCAUCCCAGGAGGAGGCCCACACGCCAGAGGCACCCCCACCCCAGCCUCCUUCCUCAGAGAGGUGCCUGGGAGAGAUGAAAUGUACCCUAGUUAGAGGGGACAGCUCCCCACGCCAGGCUGAGUUGAAGUCUGGGCCAGCAUCCAGGCCUGCCCUUGAGAAGCCCCACCCCCACGAAGAGGCUACAACCCUUCCAGAGGAGGCACCUUCCAAUGACGAGAGGACCCCUGAAGAGGAGGCGCCCCCCAACGAGCAGAGGCCUCUGAGAGAGGAGGUGCUCCCCAAAGAGGGAGUGGCUUCCAAAGAGGAGGUGACCCUGAAAGAGGAAUUGCCCCCUAAAGAGGAAGUGGCUCCAAAAGAGGAGGUGCCCCCCAUAGAAAGAGCCUUUGCCCAAAAAACACGUCCUAUCAAGCCGCCUCCAGACUCCCAAGAGACGCUCGCGCUCCCCUCGCUGGUCCCGCAAAACUACACGGAAAACAAGAAUGAAGGAGUUGAUGUAACGUCGCUGAGGGGCGAGGUGGAGUCUCUAAGGAGGGCGCUGGAGCUGAUGGAGGUGCAGCUGGAGAGGAAGCUGACCGACAUCUGGGAGGAGCUGAAGAGCGAGAAGGAGCAGCGCCGGCGGCUGGAGGUCCAGUGUAUGAACCCAGGGCACUGUGGGGACAGGGCGACGUGUGUCCAGGCGUUUGCCGGGGCUUGCCGUGGCCAAGCCAGGCCAGGUGGGAGAAGCGGCAGCCUUGCCCUGGAGGGUUUUGAGAAGCACUGCUCCUGGAGGCCCUGGGGAAGGUCCCUGAAACCUUUGGCCAAUGUGGCUGUCCCCAUGGUCCACAUGCCCUCCCCACCCCCUGCCUAGCUGCUUGACUGCCUGCUGCUCCCCAGCCCACCAGCCUGUCCGUGGGUCAGCCCAGCCACCCGCUUCGGAUCUCUGCACGUGUGUCACCUGCUGUUCUGGCCCUCAUCCCAACUAUCCACCUGCCCAUCUCCUCCCUACCUCCUCGCUGCCUAUCUGCCCAGGACUUAUCUGCUGUCUGCUCACCUGCCUGCUUGUUGACUGCUUCUCUGCCCUCCUAUCUGCCUGUGAGACUAGAGAUUUGUCACCUUGGAAAGCACGGAGAGUACUGCUAAGAUGAAACACAGGAAGGACAGGCCUUGAUGGAAGGUUGGGGGGCCGAGAGAUCCAGAGCCUAUGGGAGGGGACUUGUGAGUGCUGGCAUAUUCAGGACCCAGUGCAAACCCAAGCACAGCUCUGCUCCCGGCCCCAGUGGCCAAACUGAAGGCUUGCCCUGGCUAUUCUGCCGUUGACAUGGGCCUCACCCUACCACGGGGAUAGGUCUUGGAUGGAGGGAAGAGGGAGACUCACCGGGGGCCUCCUGAGUCCUUUGAGUGUCCCCAUGACCCCAGCACCUGGGACAGCUGCUGGAAAGAGGGUACUGGCAAAAAUUUGCUAAAUGGACAAUCAUAGGCCCAGUGUGGUGGCUCACGUCUGUAAUCCCAGCACUUUGGGAGGCCGAGGUGUGCAGAUCACUGAAGUCCAGGAGUUUGAGACCAGCCUGGGCAACAUGGCGAAACCCCAUUUCUACAGAAAACUACAAAAAUUAGCUGGACACGGUAGCACACACCUAUAGUUCCUGCUACUCAGGAGGCUAAGGUGGGAGGAUCGCUUGAGCCCAGGAGAUCAAGGCUAUGGUGAGCCGUGAUCGUGCCACUGUACUCCAGCCUGGAUGACAGAGGAAGACCCUGUCUCAAAACAAACAAAACAACAGCAACAACAAGAAAACAAUAAUAGGGACAUUGAGUACCCUUUCUGGCACCUGGCACUCUGCCAAAUGCUAUGCACACUCCGCCCUUCAGUCUUCCCAGGAACCCUGUGCAGUUUGUAGCGUGGCUCACAUUUGCCAAGAAGGAAGUGAGGCUCAGCGAGGUUAAGCAGUGCCUGUGGAGUCACAUGGCUGCAAGUAGUGGCCUGGACUGGACUGCAGAGCCCAUGCUCCCCACCGCUUUCCAUGGGGCAACUCUAGGCCAUCAUUCUCCACCCCUCAGACCCAAAGCUGCCUUUUCAUAAUGCUUGCUGUUGCUCCCUUUAUGCUCCUGAAAUGAAAUUUAUGGCUAAUAUGCCAGCCUUUACAUCUAAUUAAAAAUCAUCCAAUGGUUUUUUUGUCCUUAUUAAUAUAUAAGAAAUAAAAGGUAAUGAUAAUGUGUUUGUGAAGUGCCCAGUUGCUGGGGAGGUCACAGCUCUGUGUACAGACUGAUGCUCGGGUGUGGUGGUGUCAACGUCUGAAACGAUGAAUUUGGUAAAGUUCUGAACACAAUGAAGUGCACGUUUCCUUCUCUUUACACAGUAGUUGCAUUCCUGGAAAAUUCAAUGUAUAGUAGAAUGCAUACACUCUUUGUGUUUAUAUGCAAAAUGGAGUUAGAGCCUUGGCUCUGGUAAUGAAAAACAAGCCUUUCACUUAUGUUGUGCAGGAUGUAGAAUCUGCCUUCCUUCCAGGGCUGUCUGGAGUCCCUGGCGCCACCCUUGUAACUGCCAGUCAUUGUGAUGACCAGUCCCCUCAUCCCUUCCCCCACAGUGGCCACAACAGGAAAGAUUCCCGCCCUUAUUCAUGGAGCUCAGCGUUUGAACAGGGGAGACGGGCAUGAUCAAUAAUUGGAUAUAUGUCAGGUUGUGAUGAACACAAUGAAAAAAAAAAUGAGUAAGGGGUUAGAGAAGUCCAGGUGGACAGGUGAGGGAAGGCCUCUCUGAGGAGGUGGUAUUCUGAGCAGACACCUGAAUGAGGCAGGGAGUCAUGGAAAUACCUGGGAGAAGAGCCUUCGAGAAAGAAUAACCAGUGCAGAGUGUUAGGGUCACCCCGACCAGUUCCCCUCCUUUCGCAUAGGUCUUACAAUACAGUCCUUUGUGACCUCCGCACAGCUCCCCCAGGGCUAAAGGCAACCCCCACUGCCGCCCUGCACUGACCCUUCCAGUAACUGUUUGUCCAGAAGACUUCAGCUGAACUGGCAAACAGUUCCAGGAUGCGGUCAGAACACCUGCUAACCAAAGCUGGCAAAAACAUCACCAGGAUGCAGUCAAGACACCUGCACCCCCAACUCGGUUCACACACCCCGACCCAGUUCCUCGCCCUGUAAAGCCCUGCUGCAGUCUGUAAGCAAGGCUGCCUCCUCUGCCUGUCAAGGAACAGCCUGGCAGGACAAAUAAAAAUUGCUUGCCUGUC